ACUUCCGCGUUGCGCUGCCCGAGCCGAGAGCGCGGCCAAGGCCGCUCCCCCACCCCCGGGGGCACUUGGAGGACUCGGGACUCCCCCGCAGGUCAGCGCCCGGCGCAUCUGGUGUUUUCGCUGCCGAGGAUAGGACGACGAGCGCAAUCGGGAGCUCCGCCGCCCGGAUUCCUGCUUCCCUGGGGCCCGGAGGCUGCUGCGUACCCCACUGUGACCUGGAACCCAGGGACCCGAGUCCCGACCCGGAUUAUCGUGGCGCUUUUCCCGGCCGGCUCUGGUGCUCGGUGUCCCUCCGCCGCCGCUCCCGUUUCCGGCGGGGGAGAUGGCCAGGAUCUGACCCGGGAGGAGGCCGCACCCGCGCCGCGCUCUGCGGCUGGCUCUAGGCGAUGCCGAGCAGCUCGGACACGGCGCUGGGGGGAGGCGGGGGCCUGAGCUGGGCGGAGAAGAAGUUGGAGGAACGCCGCAAGCGGAGGCGAUUCCUGUCCCCUCAGCAGCCGCCGCUGCUGUUGCCGCUCCUGCAGCCGCAGCUCCUGCAACCGCCGCCGCCCCCGCCGCCUCUGCUCUUCCUGGCUGCUCCCGGCACGGCCGCCGCCGCAGCCGCCGCCGCCGCGGCCUCCUCCUCUUGCUUCAGCCCGGGCCCCCCUCUGGAGGUCAAGCGGCUGGCGAGAGGCAAGAGGCGCGCAGGAGGGCGGCAGAAGCGGCGUCGCGGGCCCCGCGCCGGGCAGGAGGCGGAGAAGCGUCGGGUCUUCUCGCUGCCCCAGCCGCAGCAGGACGGCGGUGGCGGUGCUAGUAGCGGCGGGGGUGUGACCCCGCUGGUGGAAUACGAGGAUGUGAGCUCCCAGUCCGAGCAGGGGCUGCUGCUGGGGGGGGCCAGCGCGGCAACGGCGGCGACGGCUGCCGGGGGAACGGGGGGCAGCGGCGGGAGUCCGGCCUCCUCCUCCGGCACCCAGCGGCGCGGGGAGGGGUCGGAGCGCAGGCCCCGCCGGGACCGCCGCAGCAGCAGUGGCCGCAGCAAGGAGCGCCACCGCGAGCACCGGCGGCGGGAUGGGCAGCGCGGUGGCAGCGAGGCCUCCAAGUCCCGCAGCCGCCACAGCCACAGCGGCGAGGAACGGGCCGAGGUCGCCAAGAGCGGCAGCAGCAGCAGCAGCGGCGGCCGCCGGAAAAGCGCUUCGGCCACAUCCAGCAGCAGUAGCAGCCGCAAGGACCGGGACUCGAAGGCCCACCGCAGCCGGACUAAGUCGUCCAAGGAGCCGCCUUCGGCCUACAAGGAACCGCCCAAGGCCUACCGGGAGGACAAGACCGAGCCUAAGGCCUACAGGCGGCGGCGGUCCCUCAGCCCACUGGGAGGCCGGGACGACAGCCCGGUGUCCCACAGGGCCUCUCAGAGCCUGAGGAGCCGCAAGUCCCCCAGCCCGGCAGGAGGUGGCAGCAGCCCCUAUUCUCGGCGGCUGCCGCGCUCCCCGAGCCCCUACAGUCGCCGCCGCUCCCCCAGCUACAGCCGCCACAGCUCCUACGAGCGGGGCGGCGACGUGUCCCCUAGUCCCUACAGCAGCAGCAGCUGGCGCCGCUCUCGCAGUCCCUACAGCCCUGUGCUCAGACGGUCUGGAAAAUCCCGAAGCAGAAGCCCGUAUUCAUCUAGGCAUUCAAGAUCUCGUAGCAGGCACAGAUUGUCUAGAUCCAGAAGUCGUCAUUCUAGUAUUUCUCCUAGCACACUAACUCUGAAGAGUAGCCUGGCAGCUGAAUUGAACAAGAAUAAAAAAGCACGAGCAGCAGAGGCAGCAAGAGCCGCAGAAGCAGCGAAAGCUGCAGAAGCAACUAAGGCUGCUGAGGCUGCUGCCAAGGCUGCAAAAGCUUCAAACACUUCUACACCUACCAAGGGGAACACGGAAACUAGUGCCAGUGCAUCACAAACAAACCAUGUGAAGGAUGUGAAGAAAAUUAAAAUUGAACAUGCACCUUCUCCCUCAAGUGGUGGAACUUUAAAAAAUGACAAAGCAAAAACAAAGCCACCUCUUCAGGUAACGAAGGUGGAAAAUAAUUUGAUUGUAGAUAAAGCCACCAAGAAAGCAGUCAUAGUUGGAAAGGAGAGUAAAUCUGCUGCUACAAAGGAGGAAUCAGUAUCUCUUAAAGAGAAAACCAAACCACUUACACCAAGCAUAGGAGCCAAGGAGAAGGAGCAACAUGUAGCUUUAGUCACCUCUACAUUACCACCGUUACCUUUGCCUCCCAUGCUGCCUGAAGAUAAAGAAGCUGAUAGCUUACGAGGAAAUAUUUCAGUAAAAGCAGUUAAAAAAGAAGUAGAAAAGAAACUCCGAUGUCUUCUUGCUGAUUUACCGCUGCCCCCUGAGCUACCAGGAGGAGAUGAUCUUUCAAAGAGUCCAGAGGAAAAGAAAACAGCAACACAGUUACAUAGUAAAAGGAGGCCUAAAAUAUGUGGGCCUCGCUAUGGUGAAACCAAAGAAAAAGAUAUUGACUGGGGAAAACGCUGCGUGGAUAAAUUUGAUAUCAUCGGAAUUAUUGGAGAAGGUACUUACGGACAAGUUUACAAAGCCAGGGAUAAAGACACUGGAGAAAUGGUAGCCUUAAAAAAAGUACGUCUGGAUAAUGAAAAGGAAGGCUUUCCAAUUACAGCAAUUCGAGAAAUUAAAAUUCUCCGGCAGCUUACCCAUCAGAGUAUUAUCAAUAUGAAGGAAAUAGUGACUGAUAAAGAAGAUGCUUUGGAUUUCAAGAAGGACAAAGGUGCAUUUUAUCUGGUGUUUGAAUAUAUGGACCAUGAUCUGAUGGGACUACUGGAAUCAGGCUUGGUUCAUUUUAAUGAAAAUCACAUAAAGUCAUUUAUGAGACAGCUCAUGGAGGGUCUGGAUUAUUGUCAUAAGAAGAACUUUUUGCAUAGAGAUAUUAAAUGUUCCAAUAUCCUUCUAAAUAAUAGAGGGCAGAUAAAACUUGCAGACUUUGGACUUGCUCGAUUGUAUAGCUCAGAAGAAAGUGCUUGGUUGAUGCUGAUCUGGGAGAAGGUGAUCUUCAUCUGGAGGAUCCUCCUGAUGCAGAUGAGUGCAGGGAGCUUUGGGGAUUCUAGUCGGCCGUAUACUAACAAGGUAAUUACUUUAUGGUACCGUCCACCUGAACUGCUACUGGGAGAAGAACGAUACACACCAGCCAUUGAUGUAUGGAGCUGUGGCUGUAUCCUUGGCGAACUCUUCACUAAAAAACCUAUAUUUCAAGCAAAUCAGGAACUUGCACAACUAGAAUUAAUAAGCCGAAUAUGUGGGAGUCCAUGUCCUGCAGUGUGGCCUGAUGUAAUCAAACUACCAUAUUUCAACACCAUGAAACCAAAGAAGCAAUAUCGUCGAAAGUUAAGAGAAGAAUUUGUUUUUAUUCCUGCAGCUGCGCUAGACUUAUUUGAUUACAUGCUUGCCUUGGAUCCUAGUAAGCGCUGCACUGCUGAACAGGCUCUUCAGUGCGAGUUCCUCCGAGAUGUGGAACCCUCAAAAAUGCCUCCACCAGAUCUCCCUUUAUGGCAAGAUUGUCAUGAGUUAUGGAGUAAAAAGCGAAGAAGACAGAAGCAGAUGGGCAUGACUGAUGAUGUUUCCACAAUUAAAGCCCCCAGGAAGGACUUGUCUCUGGGCUUGGAUGACAGCAGAACCAACACACCCCAGGGUGUGCUGCCAUCUUCACAGCUGAAAUCUCAGGGCAGCUCAAAUGUGGCACCUGUAAAAACAGGCCCUGGACAGCACUUAAACCACAGUGAAUUGGCAAUUCUACUAAACCUACUACAAUCUAAAACAAGUGUUAAUAUGGCUGAUUUUGUCCAAGUGUUGAACAUUAAGGUAAACUCUGAGACUCAACAGCAGCUAAAUAAAAUAAACCUUCCUGCUGGAAUUUUGGCAACAGGUGAAAAACAGACAGAUCCAUCAACACCACAACAGGAGUCUUCGAAACCGUUGGGAGGAAUUCAGCCUUCUUCUCAGACCAUCCAGCCUAAAGUGGAGACUGAUGCUGCCCAGGCGGCUGUGCAGAGUGCAUUUGCAGUUCUGUUGACUCAGUUAAUAAAGGCUCAGCAGUCAAAGCAGAAAGAUGUGCUACUAGAAGAGAGGGAAAAUGGAUCGGGACAUGAAGCGUCAUUACAACUCAGGCCACCUCCAGAACCUAGCACUCCGGUGUCGGGACAAGAUGACCUCAUCCAGCAUCAAGAUAUGAGGAUCUUGGAGCUAACGCCAGAACCAGACCGGCCUCGAAUUCUGCCUCCUGACCAACGACCUCCCGAGCCUCCUGAACCACCACCAGUCACUGAGGAAGAUCUAGAUUAUCGGACAGAAAACCAGCAUGUACCCACCACCAGUUCUUCAUUAACUGACCCUCAUGCCGGAGUGAAGGCAGCCCUGUUACAGCUGCUUGCUCAGCAUCAGCCCCAGGAUGACCCCAAAAGAGAAGGUGGGAUUGAUUAUCAAGCAGGAGACACUUACGUGUCCACUUCAGACUACAAGGACAACUUUGGAUCCUCUUCUUUCUCUUCUGCUCCUUAUGUUAGCAAUGAUGGUCUAGGAAGCAGUUCUGCUCCACCACUAGAACGACGUAGUUUCAUUGGAAAUUCAGAUAUUCAGUCUUUGGAUAACUACAGUACUGCUUCAUCUCAUUCUGGUGGUCCACCUCAGCCUUCUGCCUUUUCUGAGUCAUUUCCCAGUUCAGUAGCUGGAUAUGGAGACAUUUACCUCAAUGCUGGUCCCAUGUUGUUUAGUGGAGACAAGGACCAUAGAUUUGAAUAUAGCCAUGGUCCUAUUGCAGUCCUGGCAAACAGCAGUGACCCUUCCACGGGGCCAGAGAGUACUCAUCCUUUGCCAGCAAAGAUGCACAACUAUAACUAUGGUGGUAACUUACAGGAAAAUCCGAGUGGCCCCAGCCUCAUGCAUGGACAGACCUGGACUUCUCCUGCCCAAGGACCUGGAUAUUCACAAGGAUACAGGGGACAUAUUAGCACAUCAACUGGCAGAGGCAGAGGCAGAGGGUUACCAUACUGAGUAUCUGUUUUUCCUCAGGCACAUCAUUUUUAUCUGGAAAGACUUUUCUAGCUGCAAUUUAAGGCAGCAAUCCAAGAGACUUGAAUAAUAAUAAUUCAACAACAGCUUUAUUUUUAUGUGGAGAAGGGUCUUGCAUACAAUAGUUUAAAAAAGACAAAAAAAACCUUUGCUUAAAUUCAUGCUGUUCUAAAAACUAGAUCGAUUGUACAUCUUCACAAAUUCUAGUUAACAAUUUUAUUUUGUAUUCUUGCAGUUUUAAGUGGAUGCUAAUUUUAGGGGCAUAAGCCUUUUAUGGCCCUCUUGCAGAUCUUCUGAACUAUGCACAUUUGUGCUUUUUUUGUAAGUUUGGACCAACUUUUAUGUAACAAACAGCCCCUCCCCACCUCCAGUUUUACAACAAUCAGAAAGGGCACUGAUUUAUUUGGUAUUUUUCUUUUUACAAAGCUACCUUUAGUCAAAGGUCACUGUCAGUCUUUGCACCUGCUUUCAGUGUUAUUGUGAAAGGUGUACUUUGUGCUCAUUUCAGAAAAUAAAACACAACCUUUCUCUUGAUGCAACAGUUUUAUAAAAAAAAAAAUGGUCAACGUUAUUUUUGUUUUGUUUUGCAGAUUAUCAAAGCCUAGCAAAAUGCAUUUAAAUGAAAUAGUGGGUUUUAUAUGAAAACUAUGGGUGGGGUGGGGAGGGAAAGUAAGUGCCUUAACAGGUAAGCUUAAGGUCUGAAAAAAAUAGUUAACUUUUACCCCCAUUUGUCUUUUAAAGGGAAUCAAUGCAUUAAAAAGGCAAGAAACUCUGAAGUUUCAGGGGCUGCCUGUUCAGUUCCUGUUAGGUCCAUUCCCUCUGCUUGUCACACUUUCUCCUUUUCUGCCUGUCUUUGGGCUGUGUUGCCUUUCACUACCACCUUCUCUUGAUAGGGGAGUGAGAGCAAAGAAAGGGAGUAGAACUGCAAUCAGUACAUAUUGUUUGAGAAGUUCUACAAAGUUUUGUCAUUUAAAUGGUUGAAAGUAAUAGCUCCAGGAGAAUUUUAGAGUACCAUUUUCUUUCAGGCUGCCAUAUUAUCCCUGUUUCCAUUUGCCAUGGAUAAUUGGAGGGUCAUGGUAUAGAAGCAAGAGUUAAUAACAGAACUUGCCUAAAUGUGUUAAAGUUCAUGGGGGAGGGGUGGCAAAUACCGUAUUUUAAGUUAUGCAAUUGCCCUUUUAAGAAAGUCAAUUCUAUUCACUUGUUAACUAGAAACAUUGCUUAGAUUGAAUUUAUUGAAGCAAAAAGAAAAGGCAAUGAGAGAGAACUUUUAUCUUCCUUCCUGUCACAUUCUGUAAAGUUGAUUAUGACUUCUGCCAGACUUAGAGCAACAACUUUAGUUCAUUUUAACAUUUUUUUUUAAUGAAGAGCAUCAAAGAAUGGAGUAGUCCUUAUUUAAACUGUAAUGGUGUCAAGUCUCACUGUGUGCACACUCUCACACAUACACACACAAUUAUACUAAUUCUAGAAAGGAACCAAAGGUAAAUAACCAGUGUUUCCAUUAUCACUAAAUGGAAAAAUUGACUGGAAGUUAGAGUUGUGCCAAUUAAUCAUUUUGUUCAUCAACUGUUCUGGUAACUUAUUUUUUUUUAUUGGAAUCUUAAAUUGGAACAACUGUUACAGAAUGUAUAUUGCUCCAGUUCUAAAGCCAGUUAACCCUGUGCCCUCUAACUUAUGAACCUUCAUUUCAAAACAGUAUGUGGGAAGUCCUGUAGUUUGAUAAGAGUAAAAUUAUUUUAAAGAGGAUAAUUUACCAUUUUACUACUAUAAAAUAAGUUGAUAUCAGUUGACCAUUUUAUUUUUUGAUGGACUCUUUUUGUUGGGAGAAAGAAAUGAAUGGAAGAAAAAAAUAUGUUGCUUUUAUUUGAAUAUUGAUUACUAACAACUUAUAAACUACAUUGCAGGAAAUGAAGAAAUAUUUUGAAAUUAGCAAAAUAGCAACAGUAUUCAAGUAUCUGAAAUUUUAAUAUGGUGAGUCUUAGAGCUUUAGACUUUCCUAUAAGUGACAGUAUCUAAGUUAUUCUUAAUAGUCACACUUGAUAAUUCUGCUGACCAUAAGCAGCUAACCUACAGUUGAAGAUAUUUAUGUGACAUGAAUAGCCUGUGUUUUAAAAAUUAAAUAUUUUAUAUAAAAUUGAACUGUGUUUGGAUAGUUUUUCUAAUCAAACAUUUCAGUUAUAUAUUUAUGUUGGGAGAGUGGCUGGGAGGACAGGGAAAUUGUUGCUUUGACAUUGAAAAUUUGAACUAGAACUUCUAAUAUUAUCCUUACACAGCACUACUGUGAGACAUACUAGUCUUUUAUAUGUCACUUAGAAGAAAAAAUGUUGCCAAUUAAGCCACAAUACAAUGCUAAGACGUCAUCAAUUGUAAGCUGCAUCCCAGAUUCAGACAUAUUAUAUGAAAAUAUGUCUUAUAAUUGAUGAAAUAUGAUAGUAAAAAAUUUUAAUGCUUCCCUUCAUAGCAUUUAAUAUUUUAAUUCAGUGAAUUUGGAUUAAUAGAACAAAGUUGGGAAAUCACUAGUUCUGUAGGUUAUAACAGCAGUCAUCGCUGAAAAUUUGAGUGAAAUCUAAAGAACACAAAAUAUUGCUUAAAUUUUUUGGAAAAAAGCAGGUAAGUCAGACUGCAAGUUAAGAAGACAAAAAUAUAAAAGAUUUGACCUGCCAAAAGAAGAAAGUAUUUAUCUUCUCCCACGUGAAAUUCCCUUUUGUAUUUACUGACACAGCAGGUUUUUCUGCAUGCAACUCAGUAUGUUUCCUACGUCUUCAUUAUUUGUUGGAGAGUUGCAAGUCAUUUGUGAAACCUUAAAAUGCCAAUUUUAAGGAGUUGUCAUUUGUGGAAUGUGAAAUAAGGUAAUAAUUCUAGCUGUGAUUCAGAGCUUUAUUCUGUCAGCAAAUACAUAGUCAGUGCCUACAACAUGCCAGGUAGUAAUCUAGUCCUUGGGGUACAUCAAUAACCGUCAACAGUGUUAAAUCAUACUUUCAGUGUGCUGACAGUGAGCAAGAUUUUUUUAAAUGUCUGGAGAAGUUAGUGGUAUUUGCUACCCUCAGCUGUAUCUAAAUUGCACUUAAGUGAAUGUAGGGCAUGAAAAUUUGAGUAUCUUUUUGAAAUUUUAAAUUGAAAUUUGGAUAGAGAUGGUUAUGGAGAGAAAUCAAACAACUGGAAUAGCUGUUUGAUAUCACUUAAAAGUGAUAAAAUUUUAAGUUGAAUCUGGUCAGUUUGCAAUGGCCUAUUUGUAAGAAAUAUCAAGACUUCUUGAGAAAAAUGAAAAGUGAAUACAUAAAUGCUUAAAAUCUGGUACUUCUGAGUUAAGGUUUUGCUCUUUGAGCUUAAUCCAAUUUGGGAUGAUUUUUCAUCCUAGGGCUUUUUGUUUUCCUUUUUUAUUUUUAUUUUUUCUUUUUUUAGGGGAAGGGGACUUGCUUUCUUUUCCAAAAAGGUGAAUCCUUCUUGUAGGACAUAGGUAAAAAAAACAAAGCUGAAAUAUAUGUUUUGAAUAUAGAUAGCUAAUUCCCUGGGAUAUAAUAUCCUUUCAAUUUUUUUUUUUUUUUUGGCCCAGUCUGCCUUUUGAUGUUUUAAAAGUCUGAACGAGAUGUCCCAGUAACCUAAAAUUAUCCAGUCGGUCUUCUUACUUUACAACUAAGAAAAAUAAGGCUUAGAAAGAGGGAUUGCCAGAAACUUUGGCAGCUGGAUUGCCUGUGCUUGUUCCUCUAAGCCAUACCUAAAUUCUGCAGUAAAUACUUAACUUUUUAAUAGGGAAAUUGCUUCAAGAUAACUUGACCAGUGAUACGGUAAAAUAAUUAGACUAUUGGACUAAUGGUUUAACACAAGUGGCUUUAAAAAGUCUGCUUAAAAAACAAUUUUUAUUUAGAAAAAAUAGAAAAAUAAAAACAUCUUCAAAAUUUAGGAGCCUGAAGGGGCUGUUUGUUUCAUAUAUGGAUAAUCUUUGAAAAGGCAAGUCCUGUAUGUAUUUUUCAUUUGUUGAAAGAAGAUUGGUUAUCAGUAGGCUUGCAAACAUAAUUUGCUUUUAAGUUCUUUCAAGGUUUUAUGCAAUAAAACCUAUUGAUUUGGAACUUUAAAAAAAAAAACAACAAAAAAAUACUUUCAGGGUUUUGUAAUUUCAAGUGGUUUUUUAAGGGGAGCAAUAGUUUGCCAUUUACCAAAGGCUUCUCCAGAUAAUUUCUUAAAUGUUUCUACUUAAAAAUAAAAGCUAUUAAUAAUAAGCUGUCAUGGGAUCCAUUUGAAGACAGGGAAAAUAGAAAAUUUUUAUUGUAAAGGGAAGAACUUAUCCUUUUAAUUUUAUGGACUAACAGAGUCUGCAGGUCUUAACUCAUUUCAGCCUGUCAAAUGUGCAAUUAAAAAUGAAUUUUCUAAUUGUAUUCAAAUGAGGCUCUAUAGUGAAUACAGAAUCACUCUUCUAAGUUUUUUCCCAGUUAAUUUGUUUAAAAGUGUUGUACUCUCUUGCAAGAACGUUUAAAAGUUAAGUCUUGUAACUGUUAACAUCUAAUGUAUUAAUAUAAGCCAUUUGUUUUUUACCAUUUUUUUAAGGCCGUAUUCAAUAGUCUGUAAAUAAAUUGCCGUAACACUCCCA